CAAAGACCUGGGUUGAUAGAGACUCAGGGAGGCAGUUGGAUCUCAAAGUUCCGAGGGUCUGGGAUCUAACGGUGAUAGUUCUAGUGAAACCCUCCCACCCUUCCAGGAGACCCAUUCCUAUAAGAAAUAUGACUGAAGAGCCCAGCUGUCUCACUUUGAUAACCAAUUCUUCCAUUUGCAUUUCCAUUGAUGUGUAUUGGGCCAAGAGCAGAGCUUUUUCUUGUGGUUAAUAUCUGUUUAAUCCAGAAGAAGACCCUAAGGAAAGAGCUUGAGGAAGAGAUGACUGAAGCCAUUACAGAAGCAGCAGUAGCCUCAAGUGAGGAGGUGUCAGAGGAAAGAGACGACCUGGGGCCUCUUGAAUUACAUGACAGUGGUACCUUUCAACAAGUCGUGAACCUUCUGGACAUCAUUGACAGCGAGUCAGCAAAGACGGACACAACAGGGGCAGGCCUUGACAUGCGGAAGACCCUGGCCUCGGUGAUAAUCAUGGAGAAGGCCACCACUGAGCCUUCUGUAGUGAUAAACACUCUCAUCCGCUGCCUGCAGGUGCCAGAGAUUUCCACCCAGCGCAAGGUCAACAUUUACAACAUCCUCCAGGACAUCAUCCAGCAGGAGGGGGAGCUGGAGGAGCAGUGCGUGCAGAGGCUGGUGGCCAUUGCCUCCAAGGAGAUGAGGGAGAUCCCAGAGAUGGAGGGCUAUAUGAAGGCAGAGGUGGCCAGCGACACACUGGUGGCUCUGUCCCGAAACCACUUCAGCUUGGUCAUGUACGAGCUGCAGCACCACCUCAAGCCCCUCAACCUCACUGAUGAAUUUGUCAUCAUCACACUGGCCAAGCUGGCCAACGGCAAUGUGUUUGAGUUCAUGCCAUACAUGGGCAUCACCCUGGCUACCAUAUUCACCAUGCUGAGACUUGCCAAUGAAGCCAAGAUACGCCAGGCGAUCUGCAGUGCCAUGGAGACCUUCUGUGAGACGGUGCAGUUUUAUCUGAAGCACCUGGAGGAGAGCGUGUACCCCGUGAUGACUGAGGAGGAGUUUGCCCUGAAGGUGUUCCCCAUGUAUCGCUACUUCGUGACAGUGUGGCUGAGGCACUACAACCCCGAGGUGAAGCUGGGGGUGAUCAAGUCCCUGAAGCCCAUGCUCGGCCUCCUUCUGCCCAACGAUGACCUGCGGGAGCAGGUCUACGACUACAUCCCCCUGCUGCUGGCGGAGUACCAGGGCAGUCUGGAGGUGCUCUUCGUCACGCAGGUCUUGAGGCAGAUCCUGGAACUGUCAGUCACCACCAACACCCCUGUCCCCCAAAUGCAGCUACACACCAUUUUCACAGAACUGCACGUCCAGGUGUGCAACAAGGCCCCGGCCCAGCAUCAGUACAGCAGCCAGAAUCUGAUGGAGAUGGUGCACUGCUUCGUAGCCCUUGCUCGCUCCUACCCCAAGGAGCUGAUGAAGUUCUUCUUCAGCCAGAUGGAGACAAACAAGGAGGCCGUCCGCGUGGGGACUCUGAAUCUGAUUAGGGCUAUAGUGAGCGCAGAUGAGCCCAGGAUGAGUAUCAGGGCCAUCUACCUGGCUAUCCGGGUAGUCAAGAACACCAUCUCUGAUACCCGGUCCAAGGUGAGGAUGGCUAUUCUCCACAUCAUUGGGCAGUUGGCUCUCUGUGGCUACCAGGAGAGAAUCAAAGGCUGGGGCCUGAAGUACCUGUCUGUGCAGCUGACCUUAUCCACCUACAAACUGACAAAUCGCCGGGAGAAGUUUUAUCAGAGGGACUUGGAGGAGAGGAUGGUCCACAAAGUCACCAUGGACACUGUGAAGAUCAUUACCUCUUCUGUCAGUGGGAUGACCACCGAGUUUUGGGUGAGGCUGCUGUGCUACAUCAUGGAGACAGACUACGUGGAAGCUUUGACUCCUAUCUGUAUCAGCCUCACAAACCUGGCAGAACACCAGCUCCAUGGCCAGGAUGUGGAUGUCAGCGUGGCUGGCAAGAGCAGGCAAGUGGACCUGCCUGCACCUCAGAAGCUGCUGGCCCGUCUCCUGGUGCUGAUGUCAUCACCUUACAAGGGGGAGGGUCGUGGGAUAGCCAUGCUCAACCUCUUGAGGACCCUGAGCCAGAGCAUCGCACCCUCCAUGGCCGACAUGUGGGAGCUGGAGAUUGCGCUACUGGUCCGGUACCUGGAAGAACAUACUGAGUUCACUUGGGAUCAGAAAGCCUGGGAAGACAAGCUGAUUCAGUUUCUGCGAAACUCCCUCAAGAAGACCCGGGGGUCUAGCUGGAGCCUGCGCUUGAGUAAAGAGCUGAACAACCAGAUUGCGAGCUUUGACAGCCCCUCUCUGGAGAAGGGCUUUCUGUACCGGGCCUUGGGCUUCACCUUGGCCACAGGCCUGGAGGCCAGCAAGGUGGAGGUCCUGCUGUUGGAGCUGCUGUACAAGACGGACUACAGCAAUGACUUUGACAGCGAGGGUGUGAUUAUGUGCUUUGGCCUGUGUGCCCGGGGCCAGGUAAAAACGGUGCUGAAUGUGCUUCAUGACUUCGAGGAGAGGAUCCAGGAGUCAGAGCAGUCCUGGCAGAUCAGUGCUUGGCGGAAGGACCAUCCCUGGAGGCGGGAGACAGUGAAAAGUGCCCUCAUGGUGAUGUAUAGCUGCGUGGCCUCCUACUGCCACCCCCAGUUGCUCCUCAACCUCGUGGACAGCCCCAUCACCGCUAAGAUCAUUCACCAUUAUGUCAGCAGCUGCCAGGUAGCCCCAUCUGCUGCCUGGGGGGAUGUCUUCUGGACCAGGCUGGACAUCUGUCUCAAAAUGGCCUUCAUGAAGAGUGUUGUGCAGGUUACCAAGGCCAUCAACAACAUCAAGGACCUGGAGGACUUUCACUUUGCCCAGAAGACGACUCUUACCAGCAUUAUAGUGGCGGUCAUCAAGGCAGAACCGACUGACAACCUGGUUUCUCCAGUGCGAGCCUUGGCGAUGGAGGCCCUCUCGCACCUGAGCAAGCUGAAGCCUUUCUACUCCACAGAGGAAAACAGUGAGCUGAUGGAUAUCAGCAUACAUUCUGUAAUUUCUCUCCAACUCCCAGGAGAGGACAAUGAGUCCAUUAAGACCCUGUAUGCAAAUGCCCUGAGCUCCCUGGAGCAGCUGAUGGAGAGCCUCCUGCAGAGGCAGCUGGACCCCAAGGGGCUGCAGGAGAUGGUGCAGCUCCUGGAAAAGUGGAUCUUGUCGGAGAAAGAAUGGGAGCGGGAAAAGGCCGUGAGCCUCCAUCUCUAUCUCAUGUGGAUUUAUGUCCACAGCACUGCUGUCUGUAUCCACCUAAAGCUGGGGCAGUUUGGCACAAUGGUCGGACUCAUUGCCCCGUGCACCUGUGAUGCCCAUCAAAGAACCCGCAUGGCCUCAAUGAAUGUCCUGUCCAGCCUGCUAGAUCUUCACGCAAGCCAGACCUGCUCCUUGUGGGGCCCUUCCAAGCAGAAGGAGCUUGAGAAAUGUAAGGGGGACCUCCAGAGCACAGAUGUGGAGAAGAUCUUCUGUGCAUCCUCCAGAAUCGCCAAGGUGGUCUGCAUGGAGUUUAGCUGCGAUGAGGUGGUCUCGCUCAUCCAGAAGCUCUGCGAGAACACUGGGGCCAUGAACCUGCAGCAUGACAAGGCCUCUGUCACCUGGAUAGCCUUCUUCCUCCAGAUGCGGGCCAAGGAGCUGGAGGACAAGGUGGCCGAGAUCCUGAGUGCCAUCCUGGUGCACCUGCCGGUGGUGGACCACCCAGAGGUGCGGCGCCUUCUCAUUGACGGCAUCCUGCUGCUGGCGCACCACCACCAGGAGACCAUCCUCACAUCGCUCCUGAGGCAGCCACUGCCCAUGGAGAGCCACCUGGCAGAGGUGUGGCUGGCAGUGUCGGAGAACGUGCCCUUCGCCCGGACCAUGCUCCACAGCCUGAUGGGCCGGCUGCAGUCACGGCUCAGCCCCAGAAUCAGUGCCACCUCCAAGGCUGACAUCUGGCGCCUGGCUGCGGUGGACCCCCUGAUGACCCUGUGCACCAUCCACCUUCUCAUUCAGAAGCUGGAUGAGAAUGACAAGCUCCCGGACUUCCUCCCUGACCUCAUCUACACCCUCCUGCUGCAGCUUGGAAGCAGCCACCGACCAGAGGCCGCCCCGCCGGUCUUGAAGAUGUGGAAGCUGGUCCACACCACUCCUCUGCCGGAGGAGAUGAACCUGCAAAGGGUCACUAUCAAGUCCAUGCAGCUCUUGUUCAAGAGAGUCAAGAGCCAGCACCUGGCACAUACCCUGGACGAGCAGGCAGUGUGGGACCUCCUGCAGGACGGCGGGACAUUCCUGGAGGGUGUGAGCCUGCUGGCCAGGCUGUGCAUGCAGCACGUGGAGGGCCACAGGCAGAGGCUGGCCGAGCUGGUGCUCAGGGGCAUGGACUCAGAAGUCCUGAGCUGCCGCAUCAGCAGCACAGCGGUCUGCGUGGAAUUCAUGAGCGGCCCAGUUCUGUACCAGGAGAAGCUGCUGAAGCCGGCAGCUUUGCUGCUGGAGAAGGGUGCCGACCAGGAGGAAGACGAGGCCCUGCGGGUGCUGUCCCUGCGCGCCCUCGGCAACAUGGCCCUGGGCGCCCCCAAGAAGGUGAAGCAGUACCGGAAGGUCUUGCUGGAGAAGUGCCUGGGCCCCCUGAGGGAGCCCGUGAGCAACAGCGUGACUGCCGAGGGCAUGGAGGCCCUGACCAAGAUCCUGGCUGAGCUCCGGGAAGGGGAUGUGGGGUCCUCUUUCGACGCCAUGUCUGAGCAGUGCAGGAUCUUCUUCGACAACGAGAGCGAGCUGCUGCGUCUGAAAGCCUUCAUCCUCUUUGGAAAGCUGGCAAGGGUGGUCGGGAUGUCCAAGAAGCAUUUCUUCAAAGGGGAGGUGAAGAAGGCCUGGAUCCCCCUCAUGCUGCACUCCCAGGACCCCUGCUCCAAUGCAGCCCAAGCCUGUAUGGCUACCAUGUUUCAGUGUGUGCACUUCUGGGGCUGGAAGUCCCUGGAGCAUCCCUCAGGGCCAAGUGAUACCGCUACUGAUGACAAGAUGACCGUUUUCCAGACAACCAUGUGCUCCAUCCUGACUCGGAAAAAGCCGGCUGUUCUCUACCGCUUCUUGCUAGAAACAAUGGCCUAUGUUAAAAAUAACUUGUCAAGAAUCAGAAUCGCUGCUUGCAACUUGGCAGGAAUUAUUAUGAAGCAGAUGUCUACACAUUAUCUGAAAAAGCUGGACUUCCCAGCAUUACGGAAUUCCCUCCAGGAACUACAGCUGGACCCGGAUCCCGGGGUCAGGAGGGCAGCCCUGGAGACGCUCACAGUCUUGGAUAGCUGUAGUCAGCAUGGGUUUCUGGCUUCACCCCAAGGAAUGUCCUAGGUGGUCCAAACAUAAGACGUAAACUGUCUUCUUAGUGCCAAAUGCAAGCCCUUUUUAAUUUAGUUUGUAAGAAGUUUAGUUUGUAGGAAAAACACUAUUGUAAAAUAACUAGUAUCCUUUUGUUUCCUUCCGUUGAAAUAAACCUCCACUGUCGUUGGA